AGCAGAGGGGCGGUCUGCGGGGACAACAAUGGCGGGGUUCUGGGUCGGGACAGCACCGCUGGUCGCUGCCGGACGGCGUGGGCGGUGGCCGCCGCAGCAGCUGAUGCUGAGCGCGGCGCUGCGGACCCUGAAGCAUGUUCUGUACUAUUCAAGACAGUGCUUAAUGGUGUCCCGUAAUCUUGGUUCAGUGGGAUAUGAUCCUAAUGAAAAAACUUUUGAUAAAAUUCUUGUUGCUAAUAGAGGAGAAAUUGCAUGUCGGGUUAUUAGAACUUGCAAGAAGAUGGGCAUUAAGACAGUUGCCAUCCACAGUGAUGUUGAUGCUAGUUCUGUUCAUGUGAAAAUGGCGGAUGAGGCUGUCUGUGUUGGCCCAGCUCCCACCAGUAAAAGCUACCUCAACAUGGAUGCCAUCAUGGAAGCCAUUAAGAAAACCAGGGCCCAAGCUGUACAUCCAGGUUAUGGAUUCCUUUCAGAAAACAAAGAAUUUGCCAGAUGUUUGGCAGCAGAAGAUGUCGUUUUCAUUGGACCUGACACACAUGCUAUUCAAGCCAUGGGCGACAAGAUUGAAAGCAAAUUAUUAGCUAAGAAAGCAGAGGUUAAUACAAUCCCUGGCUUUGAUGGAGUAGUCAAGGAUGCAGAAGAAGCUGUCAGAAUUGCAAGGGAAAUUGGCUACCCUGUCAUGAUCAAGGCCUCAGCAGGUGGUGGUGGGAAAGGCAUGCGCAUUGCUUGGGAUGAUGAAGAGACCAGGGAUGGUUUUAGAUUGUCAUCUCAAGAAGCUGCUUCUAGUUUUGGCGAUGAUAGACUACUAAUAGAAAAAUUUAUUGAUAAUCCUCGUCAUAUAGAAAUCCAGGUUCUAGGUGAUAAACAUGGGAAUGCUUUAUGGCUUAAUGAAAGAGAGUGCUCAAUUCAGAGAAGAAAUCAGAAGGUGGUGGAGGAAGCACCAAGCAUUUUUUUGGAUGCGGAGACUCGAAGAGCGAUGGGAGAACAAGCUGUAGCUCUUGCCAGAGCAGUAAAAUAUUCCUCUGCUGGGACCGUGGAGUUCCUUGUGGACUCUAAGAAGAAUUUUUAUUUCUUGGAAAUGAAUACAAGACUCCAGGUUGAGCAUCCUGUCACAGAAUGCAUUACUGGCCUGGACCUAGUCCAGGAAAUGAUCCGUGUUGCUAAGGGCUACCCUCUCAGGCACAAACAAGCUGAUAUUCGCAUCAACGGCUGGGCAGUUGAAUGUCGGGUUUAUGCUGAGGACCCCUACAAGUCUUUUGGUUUACCAUCUAUUGGGAGAUUGUCUCAGUACCAAGAACCGUUACAUCUACCUGGUGUCCGAGUGGACAGUGGCAUCCAACCAGGAAGUGAUAUUAGCAUUUAUUAUGAUCCUAUGAUUUCAAAACUAAUCACAUAUGGCUCUGAUAGAACUGAGGCACUGAAGAGAAUGGCAGAUGCACUGGAUAACUAUGUUAUUCGAGGUGUUACACAUAAUAUUGCAUUACUUCGAGAGGUGAUAAUCAACUCACGCUUUGUAAAAGGAGACAUCAGCACUAAAUUUCUCUCCGAUGUGUAUCCUGAUGGCUUCAAAGGACACAUGCUAACCAAGAGUGAGAAGAACCAGUUAUUGGCAAUAGCAUCAUCAUUGUUUGUGGCAUUCCAGUUAAGAGCACAACAUUUUCAAGAAAAUUCAAGUUGUGCGGUCUAGUAUGGGAGGCACUAGCCAUGUAUGGCAAUUAAGAUUAAAGUGAAUGGAAGAAUCCUUUUCAAAGUUACCGGAAACGUGGCUACAUUUCAACUGUUCCAUAGCCACGCGUGGUUAGCAGCUCCUGCACUGGGCAACUCUAAGAGGCUUUCCACCACAGCAGGUGUGUUUCCAUCAAGUUCUGUUGGACAGCAUUUGUCUGGAGGGAUAUGUGUGUAGGAGAGAAUGUUGCUUUUGUUUUAAAACCUGAAUUUCAUAUUUUUUAUUCUUUUGAUAAAUGCAGUAUUCAGAUCCUAAUUCCUUUACCUUCAGAUGUUAUUUGGACCUUGAUUAUUUCAGAAGUUCUGAGUGUAGCUAAAUAUGACUGGUUUGAUUUUUAAGAAAUGUAUGCAAGUUAUUUUCAGAGAGUGCUGCCUUACUGUGUGGAAGAAUCUGAAAAGGGCUUAAAAAGAUGGAGAAUAAAAAUUACCUGUAAUCCCAUAAUUAUUCAAUAAUUACUUUUAAUGUUUUGGUAGAACCCUUCAAAGUAUAUAUAUAUAUAUAUAUAUAUAUGUAUUUAUGUGUGUGUAUAUAUAUGUAUUUUUAUAUACAUACAUGUAGCAUUUAUACUUUGCAUAAUUAGAGUCAUAAACCUGGGAAUAUGGUUUGAAUUACUUGUGCAAGAUAAACAGCAGUAUAUUGAACACCCAUGCACACAUUAUCUAGCUUCAAUGACUGUAAAAAAUCUAUCUUCCUUGUUUCAUUUUUACCUCUACCCACUCCACACUUUCCCCAUUUGUUAAUUUUUUAAGGUAAAAUAUACAAACACACAUAUACACUUCUUACCUGUACAGUUUUUGUUUUUGUUUUUUGAGACAGAGUCUUGCUCUGUCGCCCAGGCUGGAGUGCAGUGGUGCGAUCUCGGCUCACUGCAGCCUUCAUCUCCCGGGUUCAAGCGAUUCUCCUGCCUCAGCCUCCUGAGUAGUUGGGACUACAGGCAUACACUACCACAUCUGGCUAAUUUUUUUUUGUAUUUUCAGUAGAGAUGGGGUUUCACCAUGUUGGCCAGGCUGGUCUUGAACUCCUGACCUCAGGUGAUCCACCCACCUGGGCCUCCCAAAGUGCUGGGAUUAUAGGCAUGAGCCACCGCGCCCAGCCUUACCUGUACAGUUUUAACAAAGGGAUGCUUGUGUGUAACUCAGACGACUCUAUCUUUACAUCGUCUCUUCCAGUGCACUCCCUGCCUCCUUUUGCUUGUGGUGCUACCUGCGGUGUGAUUUCUUCAGAUUGCUUUUUUGGUAAACUUUUUUUUUUUCUUUUCUUUUUAGAGAGAUGAAGUCUUGCUUUUGUCGCCCAGGCUGAAGUGUAGUGGCACAGUCAUAACUCCCUGCAGCCUUGAAUUCCUGGGCUACAGCGACCCUCCUGCCUCAGUGUCCCUGGUAGCCAGGAUUACAGGAACAUACCACCACGCCUGGCUAAUUUCUGUAUUGUUUGUAAAGAUGGGGUUUCACCAUGUUGUCCAGGCUAGUCUCGAACUCCUGGGCUCAAGUGAUCCAGUCCACCAGCCUUGGCCUCCCAAAGUGCUGGAAUUAUAGACCUGAGCUGGGCGAAACCUUGUGUCUGCUAAGUACAAAAAUUAGCGGGGGCGUGGUGGCGGGUGCCUGUAAUCCCAGCUACUAGGGAGGCUGAGGCAGGAGAAUUGCUUCAACCCAGGAGGCGGAGGUUGCAGUGAGCCAAGAAUGCGCCACUGCACUCCAGCCUGGGUGAAAGAGUGUGACUCCGUCUCAAACAAACAAACAAAUAAGCUAAACAAUCUAAUAAAAAACGGGCAGUAGGUUUGACUUAGACUUUUUAUCAGAGAAGAUAAAUGAAUGGCACAUAAGUUCAUGAUAAGAUGCUCAGCAUCAUCGGUCAGUGGAGAAACAAAAUCACAAAUCUAUACCACUACACACCCACUAGAAUAAUAUGCAUCAAGUAAUGAGUGGGUAAAUAAAAAGUGGCAUAUCCAUACUAUGAGCUUAUUCAGCAGUAACAAAGAAUAAACAGCUACAUUCACUAAUGUGUGUAAAUCUCAGAAAUAACAUGUGAAGAGACAGAAACCAGAUAAAGAAGACUAUGUAAUGUAUGACUUCAUUUAUUUGAAAUUUCUAGGGAAGGCAAAAAGUAUAAAGAACAAAAGAAAGAUCAGUGGUUGUCUGGGUCUGGGUAUGGGAGCAAGAUUGACUGCACAUGAGUUUUAUUGUUCUAAAACUGGAUUGGGGUGAUGGGUGUACAACUGUAUGAAUGUAUUACAAUCUCACUUGAUCUUAGCCAAAAGGCCGAGAAGUGAUAUAAAUGUAUUACAAUCUCAUCAGACUAUACAAUUAAGAUGUAUAGAUGUUAUUGGCCAGGUGCAGUGGCUCAUGCCUGUAGUCCCACACUUUGGGAGGCCAAGGCGGACUGAUCACAUGAGGCCAGGAGUUCGCGACCAACCUGGCCAACAUGGCGAAACCCUGUCUGUACUAAAAAUACAAAAAUUAGCCAGGCUUGGUGGCGCAUGCCUGUAGUCCCAUCUACUCAGGAGGCUGAGGCACGAGAAUUGCUUGAGCCUGGGAGGCAUAGGUUGCAGUGAGCCGAGAUCACGCCACUGCACUCCAGCCCGGGUAACAGAGCGAGACCCUGUCUCAAAGUAAUAAAAAGUAAAAUGUAUAGAUGUUAUACAAGUAAAUUAUAUCUUAAUGCAACUUAAAAAACUGUAAAUGUGGUACCAACAAAGGGCU